ACAUCAUGCCACUGGACUCCAGCCUGGGGCGACAAGAGUGAGACUCCGUCUAAAAAAAAAGGAUAAUGAAUGGCAACGCCAGUGGGCUAUUGGGCAGCAGGGCAAGACUUUUUCAGCCAGUAUGCUUUAGGGAACUGAACUUUGCUUGAAAAAACUACCUUCGCAAAAUCACCCCCAACGGCUGUAAGUUGGAGCUCCCAGCAUCGACUUGCUGCGCAAGGAGAAACACAGUCUGAAGGGGUAUUGAGGGACUGCCAAAAGCACUGCGGCUUCGUGACCGAGCCCCUCUCGACAUCACUGUCCAGGCCAAUUUGAGUUGGGUUUUUAUCCAUCGCUACUAGAGGAAUCAAUGGAUUGACUUGCUCGCUUGGAAGAUUGUGAAGUAGUUGUGGCUACGGUCAUAUUCCGAACACCUGGUGUAUGUGAGUUUCUCUGAGGACACAUAUGCCUGGCAAAACUCGGAGCAAGUGAAGGUGGACCUGGUCUCCGCUUCCUUCCUGUCCUGCGCCCCUUCUCCUCACCCCCAACACAAUGGCUCAUGCACUCUUCUUGCCUUUCCCAGGAACUGUCCUGCGUUCUGUUUCUGCUCUCACAGCAAUCAGUCUCCUGAAUAGUGAGGACCAGGUGGCAGGUGCCUUGUCUAUGGGAAGAGCACAGGACCUGCUGUGGGAAGACUUGCUUUUUAGUUCCAGCUUUGCCACUGCCCAUCUAGGUGGUCUAGGUGAGCCAUGGAACUGCUUGAGAUUUAUCUUCCAAAAAGAUAGGUGGAAAUAAUGAUAAUCCAUGAUCUUCUGCAGGAGCUCCUAGUGAGGGCCUAAGGAGGUAACACAUAGGAGUGUGUUGUGAACGGCAAAUUAACACGAAAAACAUGUUGCUGUUAAUAAGCAGCUGAAUGUGUGGCUUUCCUUGGGAAAUGCUGCAUUUUCAAAGGGGGUCUUUGAAGAGGGGCCACUCCUUCAUUCCCUACACGAGCGAAGCUGUAGUGGUGGAAAGACAGCCUUAGGAAGGGUUGUAUUAUUUUGAGGUUAAGAGGUGCUUCCUAACUGCCCAAUUAUCCCUUAGUUUUGUGGCUGACUUCAUUCCCAGGAUAGUAGUUAAGACCUGGAGGUUCCUGUUUCCUAAAGGAGGACACUUUUCUUUUCAUUAGAGGAUAUUUCUGCAGCACUCAUAAGGCAAGAAGUGGUGUUGAAAAAGGAUGGACCAAAUGAACAGCCUGGCUCCCCUUGACCCUAAGAGUACAGGUGGGGAGCUGUGCGGAGCUGUCCUUUCCUUCUUCUGAAGGAAAAAGCGACUGACACAUAAAAGAUACCAGGAUGAAGAUUGCUAGUUAAUGACUGCUAAGAACUUGAAAGCAAAUGAAGAGUUGUCCCAAAAGAAUGGGCUGGAAGUACUGAUCUCACAUGCCAAAUCAGAAGUUGGACGGACUAGCGAAGAUCCGGACUGCUCGGGAAGCUCCAUCCGAAUGUGUCUGCCCCCCAGGGCCCCCUGGACGGCGCGGCAAGCCUGGGAGAAGAGGCGACCCUGGUCCUCCAGGGCAAUCAGGACGAGAUGGCUACCCGGGACCCCUGGGUUUGGAUGGCAAGCCCGGACUUCCAGGCCCGAAAGGGGAAAAGGGUGCACCAGGAGACUUUGGCCCCCGGGGAGACCAAGGACAAGAUGGAGCUGCUGGGCCUCCGGGGCCCCCUGGACCUCCUGGGGCCCGGGGCCCUCCUGGCGACACUGGGAAAGAUGGCCCCAGGGGAGCACAAGGCCCAGCGGGCCCCAAAGGAGAGCCCGGACAAGACGGCGAGAUGGGCCCAAAGGGACCCCCAGGGCCCAAGGGUGAGCCUGGAGUACCUGGAAAGAAGGGCGACGAUGGGACACCAAGCCAGCCUGGACCACCAGGGCCCAAGGGCGAGCCAGGGAGCAUGGGGCCUCGGGGAGAGAACGGUGUGGACGGUGCCCCAGGACCGAAGGGGGAGCCUGGCCACCGAGGCACGGAUGGAGCUGCAGGGCCCCGGGGUGCCCCAGGCCUCAAGGGCGAGCAGGGAGACACAGUGGUGAUCGACUAUGAUGGCAGGAUCUUGGAUGCCCUCAAGGGGCCUCCCGGACCACAGGGGCCCCCAGGGCCACCAGGGAUCCCUGGAGCCAAGGGCGAGCUUGGAUUGCCCGGUGCCCCAGGAAUCGAUGGAGAGAAGGGCCCCAAAGGACAGAAAGGAGACCCAGGAGAGCCUGGGCCAGCAGGACUCAAAGGGGAAGCAGGCGAGAUGGGCUUGUCCGGCCUCCCGGGCGCUGACGGCCUCAAGGGGGAGAAGGGGGAGUCGGCGUCUGACAGCCUACAGGAGAGCCUGGCUCAGCUCAUAGUGGAGCCAGGGCCCCCUGGCCCCCCUGGCCCCCCAGGCCCGAUGGGCCUCCAGGGAAUCCAGGGUCCCAAGGGCUUGGAUGGAGCAAAGGGAGAGAAGGGUGCGUCGGGUGAGAGAGGCCCCAGCGGCCUGCCUGGGCCAGUUGGCCCACCGGGCCUUAUUGGGCUGCCAGGAACCAAAGGAGAGAAGGGCAGACCCGGGGAGCCAGGACUAGAUGGUUUCCCUGGACCCCGAGGAGAGAAAGGUGAUCGGAGCGAGCGUGGAGAGAAGGGAGAACGAGGGGUCCCCGGCCGGAAAGGAGUGAAGGGCCAGAAGGGCGAGCCGGGACCACCAGGCCUGGACCAGCCGUGUCCCGUGGAGAAUCCCACGUGCGGAGGCCGGAGAGGGGCACCAGGCUGGCGGGGCCCUGCGAGGGGCAAUGGGCCAUGCCCUGCGGGCCCCGACGGGCUGCCUGUGCCUGGCUGCUGGCAUAAGUGACCCACAGGCCCAGCUCACACCUGUACAGAUCCGUGUGGACAUUUUUAAUUUUUGUAAAAACAAAACAGUAAUAUAUUGAUCUUUUUUCAUGGAAUGCGCUACCUGUGGCCUUUUAACAUUCAAGAGUAUGCCCACCCAGCCCCAAAGCCACCGGCAUGUGAAGCUGCCGGAAAGUGGACAGGCCAGACCAGGGAGAUGUGUACCUGAGGGGCACCCUUGGGCCUGGGCUUUCCCAGGAAGGAGAUGAAGGUAGAAGCACCUGGCUCGGGCAAGGCUAGAAAGAUGCUACGUUGGGCCUUCAGUCACCUGAUCAGCAGAGAGACUCUCAGCUGUGGUACUGCCCUGUAAGAACCUGCCCCCGCAAAACUCUGGAGUCCCUGGGACACACCCUAUCCAAGAAGACCCAGGGGUGGAACAGCGGCUGCUGUUGCUCCUGGCCUCAUCAGCCUCCAAACUCAACCACAACCAGCUGCCUCUGCAGUUGGACAAGACUUGGCCCCCGGACAAGACUCGCCCAGCACUUGCGGCUGGGCCCGGGGAGCAGUGAGUGGAAAUCCCCCACGAGGGUCUAGCUCUACCACAUUCAGGAGGCCUCAGGAGGCCAGCCUGCCAUGAGAGCACAUGUCCUCUGGCCAGGAGUAGUGGCUGAGCUCUGUGAUCGCUGUGAUGUGGACCCAGCUCCAGGGAGCAGAGUGUCGAGGAUGGAGGGGCCCAGCCUGGACUGACUGCUACUUCCUGUCUCUGUUUCCAUUAUCACCCAGAGAGGGACAAGAUAGGACAUGGCCUGGACCAGGGAGGCAGGCCUCCCACUCAGAGUCUGGGUCUCACUGGCCCCAAGUCUCCCACCCAGAACUCUGGCCAAAAAUGGCUCUCUAGGUGGGCUGUGCAGGCAAAGCAAAGCUCAGGGCUGGUUCCCAGCUGGCCUGAGCAGGGGGCCUGCCACCAGACCCACCCACGCUCUGACGAGAGGCUUUUCCACCUCCAGCAAGUGUUCCCAGCAACCAGCUCCAUCCUGGCUGCUUGCCUUCCAUUUCCGUGUAGAUGGAGAUCACUGUGUGUAAUAAACCACAAGUGCGUGUC